CCUUCCACCUUCUUUUCAUUUCUAGUGAGACACACGCUUUGGUCCUGGCUUUCGGCCCGUAGUUGUAGAAGGAGCCCUGCUGGUGCAGGUUAGAGGUGCCGCAUCCCCCGGAGCUCUCGAAGUGGAGGCGGUAGGAAACGGAGGGCUUGCGGCUAGCCGGAGGAAGCUUUGGAGCCGGAAGCCAUGGCACACUACCCCACAAGGCUGAAGACCAGAAAAACUUAUUCAUGGGUUGGCAGGCCCUUGUUGGAUCGAAAACUGCACUACCAAACCUAUAGAGAAAUGUGUGUGAAAACAGAAGGUUGUUCCACCGAGAUUCACAUCCAGAUUGGACAGUUUGUGUUGAUUGAAGGGGAUGAUGAUGAAAACCCGUAUGUUGCUAAAUUGCUUGAGUUGUUCGAAGAUGACUCUGAUCCUCCUCCUAAGAAACGUGCUCGAGUACAGUGGUUUGUCCGAUUCUGUGAAGUCCCUGCCUGUAAACGGCAUUUGUUGGGCCGGAAGCCUGGUGCACAGGAAAUAUUCUGGUAUGAUUACCCGGCCUGUGACAGCAACAUUAAUGCGGAGACCAUCAUUGGCCUUGUUCGGGUGAUACCUUUAGCCCCAAAGGAUGUGGUACCGACGAAUCUGAAAAAUGAGAAGACACUCUUUGUGAAACUAUCCUGGAAUGAGAAGAAAUUCAGGCCACUUUCCUCAGAACUAUUUGCGGAGUUGAAUAAACCACAAGAGAGUGCAGCCAAGUGCCAGAAACCCGUGAGAGCCAAGAGUAAGAGUGCAGAGAGCCCUUCUUGGACCCCAGCAGAACAUGUGGCCAAAAGGAUUGAAUCAAGGCACUCCGCCUCCAAAUCUCGCCAAACUCCUACCCAUCCUCUUACCCCAAGAGCCAGAAAGAGGCUGGAGCUUGGCAACUUAGGUAACCCUCAGAUGUCCCAGCAGACUUCAUGUGCCUCCUUGGAUUCUCCAGGAAGAAUAAAACGGAAAGUGGCCUUCUCGGAGAUCACCUCACCUUCUAAGAGAUCUCAGCCUGAUAAACUUCAAACCUUGUCUCCAGCUCUGAAAGCCCCAGAGAAAACCAGAGAGACUGGACUCUCUUAUACUGAGGAUGACAAGAAGGCUUCACCUGAACAUCGCAUAAUCCUGAGAACCCGAAUUGCAGCUUCGAAAACCAUAGACAUUAGAGAGGAGAGAACACUUACCCCUAUCAGUGGGGGACAGAGAUCUUCAGUGGUGCCAUCCGUGAUUCUGAAACCAGAAAACAUCAAAAAGAGGGAUGCAAAAGAAGCAAAAGCCCAGAAUGAAGCGACCUCUACUCCCCAUCGUAUCCGCAGAAAGAGUUCUGUCUUGACUAUGAAUCGGAUUAGGCAGCAGCUUCGGUUUCUAGGUAAUAGUAAAAGUGACCAAGAAGAGAAAGAGAUUCUGCCAGCAGCAGAGAUUUCAGACUCUAGCAGUGACGAAGAAGAGGCUUCCACACCGCCCCUUCCAAGGAGAGCACCCAGAACUGUGUCCAGGAACCUGCGAUCUUCCUUGAAGUCAUCCUUACAUACCCUCACGAAGGUGCCAAAGAAGAGUCUCAAGCCUAGAACGCCACGUUGUGCCGCUCCUCAGAUCCGUAGUCGAAGCCUGGCUGCCCAGGAGCCAGCCAGUGUGCUGGAGGAAGCCCGACUGAGGCUGCAUGUUUCUGCUGUACCUGAGUCUCUUCCCUGUCGGGAACAGGAAUUCCAAGACAUCUACAAUUUUGUGGAAAGCAAACUCCUUGACCAUACCGGAGGGUGCAUGUACAUCUCCGGUGUCCCUGGGACAGGGAAGACUGCCACUGUUCAUGAAGUGAUACGCUGCCUGCAGCAGGCAGCCCAAGCCAAUGAUGUUCCUCCCUUUCAAUACAUUGAGGUCAAUGGCAUGAAGCUGACGGAGCCCCACCAAGUCUAUGUGCAAAUCUUGCAGAAGCUAACAGGCCAAAAAGCAACAGCCAACCAUGCGGCAGAACUGCUGGCAAAGCAAUUCUGCACCCGAGGGUCACCUCAGGAAACCACCGUCCUGCUUGUGGAUGAGCUCGACCUUCUGUGGACUCACAAACAAGACAUAAUGUACAAUCUCUUUGACUGGCCCACUCAUAAGGAGGCCCGGCUUGUGGUCCUGGCAAUUGCCAACACAAUGGACCUGCCAGAGCGAAUCAUGAUGAACCGGGUGUCCAGCCGACUGGGUCUUACCAGGAUGUGCUUCCAGCCCUAUACAUAUAGCCAGCUGCAGCAGAUCCUAAGGUCCCGGCUCAAGCAUCUAAAGGCCUUUGAAGAUGAUGCCAUCCAGCUGGUAGCCAGGAAGGUAGCAGCACUGUCUGGAGAUGCACGACGGUGCCUGGACAUCUGCAGGCGUGCCACAGAGAUCUGUGAGUUCUCCCAGCAGAAGCCUGACUCCCCUGGCCUGGUCACCAUAGCCCACUCAAUGGAAGCUGUGGAUGAGAUGUUUUCAUCAUCAUACAUCACGGCCAUCAAAAAUUCCUCUGUUCUGGAACAGAGCUUCCUGAGAGCCAUCCUCGCAGAGUUCCGUCGAUCAGGACUGGAGGAAGCCACGUUUCAACAGAUAUAUAGUCAACAUGUGGCACUGUGCAGAAUGGAGGGACUGCCGUACCCCACCAUGUCAGAGACCAUGGCCGUGUGUUCUCACCUGGGCUCCUGUCGCCUCCUGCUUGUGGAGCCCAGCAGGAACGAUCUGCUCCUUCGGGUGCGGCUCAACGUCAGCCAGGAUGAUGUGCUGUAUGCGCUGAAAGACGAGUAAAGGGGCUUCACAAGUUAAAAGACUGGGGUCUUGCUGGGUUUUGUUUUUUGAGACAGGGUCUUGCUCUGUCGCCCAGGCUGGAGUGCAGUGGCACGAUCAUGGCUCACUGCAGCCUUGACUUCUCAGGCUUAGGUGACCCCCCAACCUCAUCCUCCCAGGUGGCUGAAACUACAGGCACAUGCCACCAUGCCCAGCUGAUUUUUUGUAGAGACAGGGCUUCACCAUGUUGCCAAGCUAGUCUACAAAGCAUCUGAUUUUGGAAGUACAUGGAAUUGUUGUAACAAAGUAUAUUGAAUGGAAAUGGCUCUCAUGUAUUUUGGAAUUUUCCAUUAAAUAAUUUGCUUUUUCCUGA